AAAUUACUACACUGUAUUCAUACCUGGAGAAUAUCAUUAUGUGACUUAAAAAUUUAAGUUUCACUACUCUGAGCAUUACAUAAAGCCAUAGCAUGCUUAAAGAAUUUAUACUGCUACCUUUUAAAGUCACUAAAAUCUUUUAAAUGGUGAAUGUCUAACAGUCAGUCUUCAGGUAUACCUGACAAAGGAUGAGAAAUGAGCUUUUGUAGAAAUAGAACUUUAUUUUAAUAAAAAUGUGUUACAUUUGUGUCUAUAUUAAAUACGUACUUACAAAUUAGUAUAUAUUUAUAAAUAUAUGUCGAAUGUAUUUGAAAUAUAAUUUAUUUUGCUAAUAAUGGAAAAUAUUCUGCCUGCUUGAGGAAUAAACUUAUCUCUGGUUAGGGUCAAUUAUUAGUGUUUCCUAUGAUUAUUUGAGGUUGGGAGUGGGAGGCUGCAAAAUCAAAAUUACCAUUUUACUUCCCUGUCAAGAAUAUUGUUCCUUAUAAAAUAUGUGUGGAGCCAUAACAACCCAGGAUGGCUCUCCUCUAAGGUCUUGAAUAAGCGGCCUAAUUGAAGAGAAUGGAUACUUACGUGUCGUUACAUGAAACCCUAUUUUCUCCAGUUUAUGCAAUCCAAGUAUGUUUCUAAUGUAAUUAUUCUGAAUUAGUUUGCAUUUUUAACACUACUGAAAAAAAUCUUUUUUGAUGUGUUUUAAAAUGAAAACCUGAUCAUCCUGGUAUUCCCCUUCUUAAACGUCUUUAGUAACUUACUACUAAGUUUGAGGUCAAGUUUUAACUCCUUAACCAAGCAUUCAAUUCCGAAACAAUCUGGCCACUGUGAAAAUUUUCCACUCUCAACUCUGGUUACGUUCUGCAUCCACACCCUUCACUCAAGACUUACCUGAAGCUCCCAGAGCUUACUGAGCCUGCUUACGAUUGUGCGUUUGCUCACGGCUGGAAUGAGCUCGCUCUCACCUUGUUUGCCUGGUGAACUAUUGCUAGUUCUCUAAGCUUAUAUUGGAACAUCAUCUCCCUUUUGAAGGGUUUCUGGCCUUAAGAAGUUAAAUUAAACCCUGUGCAUACCACCUGUGCAUUUCCAUUAACGCCUUCAUUAAUCUGCUACAUAAGCAGCAAUGAUUCUUGUCUGCAGCCAAAAUUAAGGAUCAACCCCAAACGUGCCUGCAUUUUGGACAAUGUUAGCUAAAGCUAUAAAUGGAACAGCAGUGGUCAUGGAUGAUAAAGAUCAAUUAUUUCACCCAAUUCCAGAGUCUGAUGUGAAUGCUACACAGGGAGAAAAUCAGCCAGAUCUAGAGGAUCUGAAGAUCAAAAUAAUGCUGGGAAUCUCGUUGAUGACCCUCCUCCUCUUUGUGGUCCUCUUGGCAUUCUGUAGUGCUACACUGUACAAACUGAGGCAUCUGAGUUAUAAAAGUUGUGAGAGUCAGUACUCUGUCAACCCAGAGCUGGCCACGAUGUCUUACUUUCAUCCAUCAGAAGGUGUUUCAGAUACAUCCUUUUCCAAGAGUGCAGAGAGCAGCACAUUUUUGGGUACCACUUCUUCAGAUAUGAGAAGAUCAGGCACAAGAACAUCAGAAUCUAAGAUAAUGACGGAUAUCAUUUCCAUAGGCUCAGAUAAUGAGAUGCAUGAAAACGAUGAGUCGGUUACCCGGUGAAGAAAUCAAGGAACCCGGUGAAGAAAUCUUAUUGAUGAAUAAAUAACUUUAAUUAUUUUGUCAUCAAAA